AGACGCGGACAGCGCCGGGACUCGCCGCCCCGGGACUCGCGCAGCCCGCAGCGCUCCGGCUCCUCCUCUCGCGACCGCCCUCCGCAGCGAUGGACGGAGACGGUGACCCAGAGAGCGUGGGCCAGCCCGAGGAGGCAAGCCCGGAGGAGCAGCCAGAGGAGGCGAGUGCUGAGGAGGAGCGGCCGGAGGACCAGCAGGAGGAGGAGGCGGCGGCCGCCGCCGCGUACCUGGACGAGCUGCCCGAGCCGCUGCUGCUGCGCGUGCUGGCCGCACUGCCGGCCGCCGAGCUGGUGCAGGCCUGCCGCCUGGUGUGCCUGCGCUGGAAGGAGCUGGUGGACGGCGCCCCGCUGUGGCUGCUCAAGUGCCAGCAGGAGGGGCUGGUGCCCGAGGGCGGCGUGGAGGAGGAGCGCGACCACUGGCAGCAGUUCUACUUCCUGAGCAAGCGGCGCCGCAACCUUCUGCGUAACCCGUGUGGGGAAGAGGACUUGGAAGGCUGGUGUGACGUGGAGCAUGGUGGGGACGGCUGGAGGGUGGAGGAGCUGCCUGGAGACAGUGGGGUGGAGUUCACCCACGAUGAGAGCGUCAAGAAGUACUUCGCCUCCUCCUUUGAGUGGUGUCGCAAAGCACAGGUCAUUGACCUGCAGGCUGAGGGCUACUGGGAGGAGCUGCUGGACACGACUCAGCCGGCCAUCGUGGUGAAGGACUGGUACUCGGGCCGCAGCGACGCUGGUUGCCUCUACGAGCUCACCGUUAAGCUACUGUCCGAGCACGAGAACGUGCUGGCUGAGUUCAGCAGCGGGCAGGUGGCAGUGCCCCAAGACAGUGACGGCGGGGGCUGGAUGGAGAUCUCCCACACCUUCACCGACUACGGGCCGGGCGUCCGCUUCGUCCGCUUCGAGCACGGGGGGCAGGACUCCGUCUACUGGAAGGGCUGGUUCGGGGCCCGGGUGACCAACAGCAGCGUGUGGGUAGAACCCUGAGCGACCCUGCCUCCACUCUCCCCCAGCUGCCUGGAGGGGCAAAGGUCGAGGGUAGAUAGGCCUUAACUUAGUCCAUAGCGUCCUCACCUUCCCCAAGCCACACAUCCUCCUCCCAUCCCUUGCUCCGAUCCCAGCCCCUGAGCAGGGAGAGAGAAGUUUUGUUGGCAUAGGUUUGCUUAGGUAGCCGGCUUCUAGAAUGUAGAUCCGUGAGGGCGUGAGCUUGGACUGGACCCACUGCUGAUUCCCUGCACCUAGCACAGUGCUUGCCACAAAGUGGGCUCUCAAUAAAUAUUAUUUGUCCAAGGAA